CUGUCUCGGGAACCCCGCGUGGCCGCAGCAGAACCGGCAGCUCCACCCGCGGUGAGCCAGUGCCAGCCAGAGCCUCCCAGCGCCGAAGCGCACCGCGGCCGAGACGGUUCCGCUGAGCGAGCUUGGGCGCCCGGUGAGCGCUCGGGGUGGGUGACACAGCGCUGCCUCGCCCAGUUCGCCUGCCUCGGGAAGUGGGUCCGCUGGGCAGAGGGCGCCCUGGGCAGGGGUCGUCCCCGCUGAAACCUCUGGUUCCUCGUGGGCAGGAGGCGCCCCGUCCUCCUCCCAACGAGCGUAGCGCACCCAGGACACCGCGCCGGGACGCGCUCCUCGGACGGCGACCAGAGGUCCUCGACUCCCGCGUGGCCUCCCUCUUCUGCGCCCAGCCCAACUUUUUUAGGGAGGUGGCAGACGGCUGUGUACGGGGGGAAAGAAUAUGUGUUUUGCUACAAGAAGAUGGUUCUAUCUACAUUUGGGCUGCAUGAUGCUGAUCAAUCUGGUUAAUGCUGACUUUGAGUUUCAAAAAGGAGUGCUUGCCAGCAUCAGCCCAGGAAUCACCAAAGACAUUGAUCUCCAGUGCUGGAAAGCUUGCUCUUUGACAUUGAUAGAUCUCAAGGAACUCAAGAUAGAGCACAAUGUGGAUGCUUUUUGGAAUUUCAUGUUGUUCUUGCAAAAAUCUCAGCGGCCUGGACAUUAUAAUGUCUUCUUAAACAUAGCUCAGGAUUUCUGGGACAUGUAUGUAGACUGCUUGCUUUCAAGAUCUCAUGGAAUGGGCAGAAGACAGGUGAUGCCCCCCAAAUAUAAUUUUCCACAGAAAAUAACAGGAGGUAAUUUAAAUGUGUAUUUAAGAGAAUAGCAGUUUACUUUUCUUUAAAAGUCACUAUUUAAUUCUUCUGAUUUUUUUCAAGUUAUCCAACAAGGUAGCAAAUUUACCAUAUUUAGUUUUUUUCCCUAAAAUGAUAGGUUUUGAUUCUCAUUUUUACUCAUUUUACAUUAUUUACAAACCACACAAGCUCUGACUUACAAUUUUAAAUGAUCUUGGAAUAUAAUACACUUUGGUAGAUAAUUAAAAUUAUCCUUGUUUGCCCAUGAAUAGUUCAUAAGAAAGCCAUUUAACCCUGUAAUUAUUCAUAUUACAUUUGUUGAAGAAAUUUUAAACAUCAGACAUGUAUUUAGGCUUUUGAAAUUAAUUUUUUCAAUAGGGUUGUAUAAAAGCAGGAAAUUUAAGAGUCAUAUUGGAAUGAAUAUUAACAAUUUCUUCUUUUAAAUCUUACAGGACUAGAUUUUACAAAAUGAGAGUAUUACAUUUAAGAGAAAACAUGUAAAAUACCUCAAGCAAGAUGACAGCGACCUGAAAACUUGUAUUUAUGAGGUCAAAUAUUUCUUGUCAUAGUUAUACAAAUUAUUUAAUACUGAUAAACGUUGUUUUUUGUUGUAAUUGCUUUAUUGCUAUUGAAUUAUUCCAAUAUUUUCAGAUAAUUUCUCAAUUUUUUACUUAGAAGGUGUCUUUUUAAAGUGUCUUUGUUUUAAAGAAAACAUCAGUUAAAAGGCAAAUGUGAUAUAUUUUUUAGAUACAAUAGUCAAUGGAAUAAAAUUGUAACCAAUUUUAUAAGGUAUCUUAUAUAUUAAUAUUGACUAUUAAACUGUGCCAAAACUAAUGGCAGUAUUAUCCUAAAAAGUAAUAUUUAAUGUAGUAUAUUUUGUGGUUUCUGAAAUGUACAUUUCAUUACCAAGCCAUCUUCUAUAUUAAAGUAUUUUUCUAUGCAUUAAGGACUAAAACCUUUUUAUGUUCUCAUUUUUAUUGUCUUUGUUUUGAAAAAGGAACAAUAAACAAAGACAGAAACUUCAUUUCAGUAAAGUACAAUUUGAUAGAAUUUUUGUGUUAGCUGAGUUAUUUUUUAUAUUGCCUAUUUAUAUCUCACAUCUUAUUUCAAAAAGGAUGUGAAGCUUUAAAGAAAUAUACCGAAGAAAAGGAAAACAUGAAGUAGUGGAGGAAAUUGGAACAUUGGGACAUGAAGACAGGGAAGUAAUACAAUGGAGUUACGGUUUAGAUUAAUACUUUUUGAAUGCAUGUCGUAAAAGCCUAUACCUUUGAUAAAGGGUGCCUAUAAAUUUGGUCUGUUUCCCACUUCUCCUAGUGAAGAGGGACACAUGAACAGUUUCAAGAUUCACAUGCUUAUAAGAAAAACCAAACCAUAUGUUCAACAGAGGUCCAGCCUUUUCCAGGACAAAGAAUCAAUGAAAAUCUCACCCAUAGGUUUUCACAGUGGCUACCAUGGUUUACAACACUGGUUUCAAGUAUCCUUACAAUGACAGAUUCUCUCCUUUACAGUCUGAUUCCAGUACACUCAAACUCAAAUAUAAAAAGUUUUAAAAUCGGCUAAAAUAAUACUGAACAAGUAACGAACUGCCUGAUGGUUUGACUUGAUCCAAGAAUAAGCUGAAUUAAAGGAGGGACGUUCUUUGCAUUAUUGACCACUUUCAAAUUCUGAUGAUGUAUAGACCAUUUAUUAGGGGUUUUAUAUAUAAACACUCUUAAAAUUACAUUUUGCAUGUAAUUUCAGGGGGCUGCAUAAACCCCAGGUUAGGAAUUUUCAAUAUUAAAGGACCUCAUAGCGUUCGGCAAUAUUAUUUCAUAUAACCAAUUUUGCAUGAGUAGCAGAUAAUAUAAGAUUGUAGGGCUAAUAAUUUCCUAGAUUGAAAACUUCUUAUCUUGCCAAUUAAGGGUGGAUCCCUAAGCUCAGAAAAUCAACUGGUUGGAGGGUAGGGCUAAUUAAUGUUCUCAUAAAAAUGACCAGACAGCGUGUAAACAUGAGUGAUUUUAUGUCCAUUAAGCUUUUGAUUUGUGGAAUUUAUAUGACAAAUAAUUAGUCUGAUAUGAGUUUUUAAAUUUCAACAUAUUUUCAUAUUGACACUUUAUUACUGUUUAGCUCUAAUCGAAAAGUGAUGAUUCAUUUGAGAGGAGUCACAUUUAUGUGACAGGAGUAAAAAGUUGAGUUAAUCUUGCCAAGAACUUUCCUGUCCUUUCUCAUCUCCAUAUUGAACAUCUGUGUUCUUUAUCAUUAAACUGCUUUUGGUCUAAAAAAAAAAAAAUGACCUGACAGCUAUCCACCUAGAAUUCAUUUCCUGCAGAGGAGCCGAAGUGGUACCUAGAGGCAGUAUUACAGUUUUCCUCAAAAAAAACAGUUCUCUUUUACAGUCUGUGGGCAAAUGAUUGAAGCUCAAAAGUUCAAUGCUGUAAAGUGAGACCAUGUACUUUUAGUCUAAAAAAUUGUUCAACCAGUUGUCCUCAAUCACUCAUAGUUGUCAUGACAAUUUUAUUGCAGCGAUGAUAAACAUUUUAGCUUAAAUCAAUAAAAUUAGUCUUCCAGUUAAUGG